AGUAUAGCCGAGGGACAGAAUGUCUCAGUAAGACGGGCUCGGAGGGGAAGUGUUUUGGAAAGGCCUCUGCUUGCUCUGGGAGGCGUUCAGGAUGCUGAGGUUUUGGAAAUCUAUGGCGGCUCUUCACAACUGCUCCCAGCUUUGGGAGGAGGAAUAGACGGGUGCUCGUUUCCUCGGGUUCAGUGGCAAAGGUGAAGACCAGCACUGCCGACCUGGGACCUGGGCCUCUCCCGGGCCUGGGGAGGACACUGGACUUUGAAGGGGAAUGCAGCCUAGAAGGCCUGGACCCUGGAGUCAGGAGAUGCUGCUCCCAUCCAGUAAGCCCUGGCUGGAGCUCUUCUGGGCACCAACCCUGGCAUAAAACCAGUGGGGCCUCUGGGCCUGCACUCAACAGUGCCUCUGAUGGAGCAGGUUCAGCUUGGUUGUGACCUCUGCUAGAAGCCCUCCCUGGCCUCCCUGUGCACUGAGCUGGUGGUUCCUCCUUUGCGCCCCAGUGCAUUUCCCACUCUUCUCAGCUUGGAUGGUCUGCAAAUUCUACCAGCCACAUAUCCACCCAAGUUCCUGAUAAACAUGUCGAAGGGGCCAGGACCAAAGCUGUGUAAGAAGCUCUCGCCACACCACCACAGGCAGGCCUCAAGGCCCAGCGCCUGAGGAGUCACAAAGCCUGCAACCUGAACUGCUUCACCCUCCAGGCCUGCAUGGCAGAGGACGCUAUGAAAGGCUUGCUGGAAUCCAGCCACGGGAGCCUGGCCAUUCUAGUGUCCUCCCUCAGCCCAUCAGCCGGACACGGAGGCUACCUGGAUCAGAUGCUGAACUCCUUCAUGGCUUACUGCAUUUUGGAUGGACAAACCCAUCUUUUCUCAGUGCAUGUCCAGAACUGUGGUAUCAAGUUCACAGAUAGGUAGAGCAGGUUUCUCUCCGUGCCCCUUCCUGAGACUCAGGCCUCCUUGGUGACUAUGCUGCAGUUUGGCAAUCUCUAGGCCAGGAGACCUAUGUAUGUAUAUACCUGUGACCCAGAAGAUAGGGUGGAGGUAGGCAAGGAGUAGGCAAGGGGUGGAGAGUUGGGGAGAGGCGAGACUCGUGGGAAUUUGGUUUUCCUUAAGGCUGGAGUUUGGAAUAAGUGGUCAAUGUAACUGGCCGUAAGCCUUGGAAUGAAACUCCUCCUUUCCCACUGGCAGAAAGGGCUGAGCCGCCGCCUUGCACAUCCCAGGCUGGAACUUGAGCCGCGCAGCUGGCUGUGUGCAAAGUGGGGAAAGAGGGGAAGAGGGGACUCUAACAAAAAUGUUCUGGGCCUGGCUGGGAAUGCUGAGCACAGAAAUUUGAUCGGGGACUGAAACAACUCCAAAUGUUUCCCACAUUUCUUGGAAAUGGAGGCAUUCUCACCAGAACCUGGGUUUUCUUUUGAAUAACACUUCCCCCUAAACCUGUCCCCCACCCUGAGAGGGUGGGAGUUGGGACGGGAAGCAAGCAUUUACCAUGCCAUCAGCGAUCCUGGGCUGUUUGUCUCUGAAAUUACCAUCAGCCAUUAGAAGGGAAAAGUGGGGAGGCUUUGCAGAAGAGGUGCAAGAACCACCCAGCAACCCCAACUCGCUCCGCUGGGCUGCUGAGGUCCAGAGAUUUAUGUUCCUCCCUCUGCCCUGGUUCUAAAGCUCCUCCUCUGAGUUCAAGCUGAGUGGAGCUGCCUCCUGCCCUCCAAGGGCAGCUGUCCUGCAGCUCGCCCCUCCCUUUCUCUAGCUGUCCACCCCUUUGGCCUCUGCUCCCUGACUCCUGCUCUUUCAGGGGCCAUGGGAGAGAGAGGCCUGACCCCUGGAUUUUCACUGCCACCUCUUAGCCAUUAGCCUGGCGCCUGAGGCCCUCGUCACACCCCAGGCUAUGCUUGGGGCUGGGAGCCCUUUGCUGCCCACGCCUGCCCCUCUCAGGAGCUGGAAGAAGCCGCUGCUAUGAUAGAAGUUUCCAUCAGAAAAAGGAGAGGAAGUGAAGGUUGCAGAAGGAGGAGAAAACAAAAGCUGUGUCAGUCUUUGCCCAUGUCCAGAUCUGGAGCCGGACAAUCGCCCCUCGGGGGCUCGGCUUUGAGCCACAGCUGUGUCUGCCCUGUGGAAGGAGGAGCAGCCUCCCCCCACCUCUGGUUUUCCAUGAGGUGGAAAUGGGGCACCUAAGGAGAGGCACGAGCAGUAACAGAACCCUCUUCAUACAUAUUAUGCCCCCCAAGAAAGCGCGGGGCCUGGGUUCAGGUCCACUUUGUCAUGAGCUGACUCUAGGGGACAGGCCCCCACCCGGGCUUCUCUCUCUUGUGGAUGUGGACUGUAUGGGUACACAGGGUUGUGCCAGAGGUUCCAGAUGCUGCAGGACAAGCAUGGCUCAUCCUGGAGAGCAUCAGGUUUGCCAGACUGUAGGAAGAAAAGCACCAUCAUUUUUAUAUUGAAGUAGCCAUGUGUAUAUUAUGAAGGAAGAUGCAAAACACAUAUCAAUUUUUAAGAAAACACCACUUUUCCAACAAAUCACACCAUUGGAGCCCCUUGAAGCUACUCCCUCGGAUGCUCACUCUCCACUCCCUUCAAAUACACCAGCCCUCUGUGCCUCAGUUUCUUCGGCCAAGAAGUGGGGUAGUGUUAACCCCACGUAUGAGGAAAGGCUGGUGGGGCUGGGUGGAGGUGGGGUGGGACGGAGCUGGGCGGAAGCAGGCCUUUCCUCCUCCUGGGCCUGCAGCUUGCAAACUCCAGUGCUGUGUCCCCAGAGGAAACCUUCAUUGAAUGGGUCACUGGGCUUCCCCCAGCUGAGCUGGGUGUGACGAUCUCCAGCUCUUGGCCAUGUGCCUGGUCACCCAGAUCCCAGUGGCCUGGAGACUUCCUGCCUGAGCCUCUUUGGGCUGAGGCUCCCAGGGCAGGUGCAGUGUCUCCAACAGGGGACAGCCCUGAGGCAGGGCACAGGUAUGUGGGCAGGGACUGGGCACCCCCAAGCACUCCUACCUGCUCCUUUCAUUCACUGGCCCUGGAGAAGCUGGGAGAAGAGGGUUUGAGGGGAGGGAACAGGGCAUUCCUUCUUCUGGAGGCUCAGAGCAUCAGGAAGAAGGUUGUGAGCUGCCAACCUGCUGCUGAAGCUGGCCCGUACCUAAGUUAGCCUGGCCCACAUCAGACUUUACAACUUGGAAAUCCCACCCAAAAGGAUGGAUUUCUUUUCUUUAUUUUUGACGGAGUCUGACUCUGUCACCCAGGCUGGAGUGCAGUGGCGCAAUCUUGGCUCUUGCAACCUCCACCUCCCGGGUUCAAGCAAUUCUCCUGCCUCAGCCUCCCGAGUAGCUGGGACUACAGAUACACACCACCAUGCCCGGCUAAUUUUUGUAUUUUUAGUAGAGAUGGGGUUUCACCUUGUUGGCCAGGUUGGUCUUGCACUCCUGACCUCAGGUAAUCCACCCACCUUGGCCUCCCAAAGUGCUGGGAUUAGAAGGGUGAUUCACCGUGCCCAGCCUGGAAUUCGUAUUUCUCUUGAAAAGCUCAGGCCUGACCAUCUCGGCCCAUAUGGCACUCACAGGCCACAGUGUGCAGUGACUGUCCUGUCGACAGCAGGCUUUGCCACAGGCCCCACGGCCCCUAAUGCCCCACGCAAGGCACACCUGUCCACUUCUCCCAUGCCCAUCACCUGCCGGUGGUUGUGGGCUGGAGUGUGUGGUCUCUGACGACAUCUCCCGUGAGGAGAGACGUUUGGUCAGCUGGGGCAUGACCCCCACAGCCCAGAGAAUGCUCUUUGAAAGUCAGAGCCUUUCUGACCCUCAGGCAUGGCUGGUGAGAGCUGGGUGGCGGGGGAAGGCCCCAGUGCCUCCUCUUCCCACUCCCAUGGGGCACCGUCAGCCCUUCACAUUGCCCUGGGCUUUGGAGGGACCUGGGGCUGCAGGCAGAGAGCCCUGAGGGAGCUACAGUUCUGUUGGGGCUGCUGGAAAGAAACAUGUCCCAUCCCUUGAGCCCCUGACCCUAGUGACUGGCAUCCCCUACACUGCCCCAAGUGGGUGAGGUGUCAGCACUGACACCCGCCUCUGCAGAUCUCCCAGGCAGUUUCCCUGAAGGCUGGGAGCUCCCAAUUCCCAAACAUCCCCAGGCUGUGGGUGGCCAGGGGGUGAGGCCAGGGCUCUUUGUGUCUCUGCCUUUUCCAGACACUGCCAACCUUGUCAUUCAUUCAUCACAUAAUUGUUGGGUGCUUACUGUGUGCCAGCAAAGACGUGAGGCACCCCUUCUGACUGUGUGACCUCAGGCAAACCACAAUCCUUGCACCUCAGCUCUCUUAUCUGUAAAACUCGGAUAAACUCGGAUAUGACAGUAUCUGAUUUAGGAGGUAGUUAUGAGGAUUACAUGAGAUGAUGUAUGUCUCCCAGGCUGGGCGUGGAGCCGGUACACAGCAAGCGCUCAAUAAAUGUUGUCCAUGUCACAGGUACCAUUACUAGUAAGAACGGGCCAGCUUCCUGCCCCUUUGGUGUCUCUCCUUCUCUGGCCUCCAUUCUCGGCUUCUGUUCCUCUUCUCCCUCCCUGCUCUCCGCCAGAGGCCCUAAGUCUGCACCCUGAAGCGGGGCUGCGGCCUCCCUGGAGUCCCAGGCCCACGGGCGGCCCCCGCCGGCCCCCUCCAGGUGCACAGAGGCCCCAUUCUCCAGGCGCGCGUCCCCUCGCCCGCUCCUGGGGGACCCUGCCCGGUGACCUCGCGACCCCGCCGUUUGCGCGGACAAAGAGGGGCCUUUUGUUCUCUGGCCAGGCCUGCCCGGCCCGCGCAGCUCCCGCCCUAAUCCGGCUAAUUACGGUCCACACGGCGACCGGGGCGCGCGCUCGCCCACCACUUUCCCACGGCCGCGAAGAAAGCCCCUCAGUGCGCGCCGGGAACAGAGCGGCGAUUCAGCUGCGCCCUGCGCCGUGCUGCUGCCGUGGCCACCCUUCGCUGCGUCUUCUGCCGUUCCCUUGUCCUCUACCUCUGUCUGUCGGUCUCCGGGCCUUCCACCCGCCGGCUGUUUCUCUUUUGGUCUCCCUCUCUGUGUCUCCCCAUCUUUCUCCCUCUCUGUGUUUUUAUCUCUGUCUCUCCCCGGCGUUCUGUUAUCUGUCUGUCCCAUUCUCUCUGCCCCUCUGCCCCGAGGCCUUCUGCCUCUGUGUCUCUGUCCCCUGGGCCUCUCCCAUGGCGGGGGUUCAGCCUGCCCCUCACUGGCUCCACGUGGGGUCCCAGCUUAAGCUGAGCAUCAGCUUCCCCAGCCCAGCAGCCUCGGGCCUCCGUUCUCUCCCCGCUGGGGACCCCAGGGUCCUGGCCCCUUCUAAGGAAACCAAGGAAGCUCUGGGGCCGGGCCAUGCCUCCUAAAUGGUUUUGGGGAAAGCUCCAAAACAGAGAAGUGCCUCAAGAUGUCCGGUGCUGGCCCAGGUGUUGGGGGAGGGGGCGGGGAGGGCUCCUGCAGCAGCUCCUGCUGGUGUGCUGUGGCCAGGUCAGAAACGGGAGCCACUCUGAAGUAAUCUCAGCCUUGGGGACAGCCAAGGAGAGAGUCUGGUUUGUGCUUGACUAGUUCCAGACCAGCCACCAUAGAGUCCAGACAACUGCUUUUCUAGAAUUCACUGUGAAUAUGUGUCUAAAGGGUGCUGGACAGGCCACAGAAUGGGUCUUUUUGGCAGAAGAAAUUCAUUCAUUCAUUCAUUUUAGGGCCCAAGAAAUUCAUUCAUUCAUUCACUCAUUCGCUCAGCAAGUAUUUACAGAAUGUUUACUAUGUGCCAGAGAUUGUUCUAAGCAGCAAGGAGAAAGCCAUGAACAAAAUGAAGAUCGUUGUGCUGCAUUCUAGCAGGGAAGGCACAUGGGUGAAAGGUAAGAGAAGGAGAUUGACAGACGGUGGGAACGGCUAAGAAAAAACGCAAAACCGGGUGGAGGUCGGCCGGCGUGGUGGCUCACGCCUGUAAUCCCAGCAGUUUGGGAGGCCGAGGCAGGUGGAUCACCUGAGGUCAGGAGUUUGAGACCAGCCUGGCCAACAUGGUGAAACCCCAUCUCUACUAAAAAUGCAAAAAUUAGCUGGGCGUGGUGUUGCACGCUUGUAAUCCCAGCUACUUGGGAGGCUGAGGCAGGAGGAUGGCUUGAACCUGGGAAGCGGAGGUUGCAGUGAGCCAAGAUCAUGCCACCGCACUCCAGCCUGGGCAAUAGAGCGAGACUCUGUCUCAAAAAAGAAAAAAAAAAAAAAAAAGGAGGUGUCAGGAGCUGGAACGGGGUCAGAGGUGGCCUAUCUGGGUUGGUGACACUGGAGCAAGACCUGAGUAAUGUCAGGGUGUCCUCCCUCCAGGGCAGUGGCUGGGUCUGCAGGCAAGUUCCCACCAAAGCUGCCAGGUGGCUCUUCCUUCUGUCCUCAGGUCCCAGUCGCUGGGAGACGCCGAGACCCACUGAGGCCCGGUGGUGGCCCCCAGCUCACUGAGGGGCAAUGGCCGGGAAGAGGUUGGCUGAAAGACUUGUGCUGCAGGAAAACUCCUCCUGUCCCUCAUUUUGCUUCCCUUUUUCUCAUCACUGUCAGGGGUUUUCUGACAAUGAUGACCUUUGAGCCACAAAUAAACCACACAGCCACAUGGGAGGGGUCCUGACCAGGGCCUGGUGGUCUGUGUCCCAGGGAGAAGUACAGCCCUCCUGUCUGCAGAGAAAGUGAGGACUUCUUUACAUCAAGGUAAUUGAGGGAGAAGGAUUAGUGAGUUUUCUGAGCUCAUAAAUCACAAAACAACCCAGUGGUGUUGUGGGUGUCCAAAUCAGGGGGGCAAGAAAGACAGAAAAGGGCAAAAAAAAAACCACAAACAAAAACACUCUGGUGGGGUCAUGUUGGCUUUGGACAAAGCAAGAGAACCUGGGGCGUAGCCGAGGCGGGACUAAAGGAAACACCGUAAGACCCAGAGGUGCUGGGGCUGAGAUUUAGGGCACUGAGGGAGUUUGAGAGCCAGCCAGCGGGCGCCAUCACGAGUGUGUUGGGUAUACGUGGUUUGUGUGUGGCAUAUGGGAGGAUGGAGCAGGCCCGUGUGACCUUCCUCAACCUCUCCCGCCAGCUGGCUCCCCUGCCCUCAGUGCCCUACCUGGCAGAACCUGGUCCUGGCUGAACUACCACUGAGCUUAUGUGACCCCUCAUCCUGCCAAGCCAAGGUGGGGCUGGCCAGGUUUAUGGGCCCAGACACCUUCACACCUGGACCUUUUCCCCUUGGGACUUUGAGAAGCAGACAAGUGCCACAAUUCUGUGUGGGGCUAAAGGAAGAAAUCCCCAGCUAGGUCCGGGAGACGGUGUGUUCCUCAUGGCCCUGCCCCUCACUAACUGGGGGCCAUAAGCGCACCAUUUGCCCUCUCUGGGCCUCACUUUCCAUACUUGGAGAAUAGGAAUGGUACUAAUAAUCGUCCCUCUUCACAGGGUUACAGUAAGGAUAGAUGAGACUGAGAUGUAAAAUGUAUUCUGUCAGCCAGUGAUCACAUCUUGUUUGACCAAUACAUGUAAAAUUUUGACCUAUUACUCACACAUAUAAUCGAAACAAAAGUUUAUACUUAUCUGUUAUAUUCUGUUGAAUGCAUUGAUCUAGUCUAUCCUGUUCUGUUUCUUUCUAUUUUUUAAAAAAUCACAGAUCAUAAUGCACUGGGUCUUGAACUACAGUUUCAGAAACACUGUCAUAAACCAUGGAAGGGGAUAUAAAAGCAUUUGUGGUUUCAUCACCUAGAGAGCUUGCUGGAAGUGGGGCCUGGAGUAGCCUUGGGAGCUGCCACCCUAGGCACACCAAUGGUGACCCCAGUGCCACUCAUCACUGGCCUAUGUGGGCCUGCUCCUCUGUGGUGGACUUGAACCUUACUGCUCCAGCCAUCUCCCCUGCCUGCCUGUCAAGCCUCGCUGUUGACUGUAGUCAUCUUCAUGCCAAAGGCCAGACAUAGCCUGCGAGACUUGGAUGGGACCUCGAGGGUCAUCUCAUCUCUCACUUUAUAUAGGAGAAAACUGAGGCCCAGCCAAGGAAAGUGACUUAUUCAAGGCUGCCCAGUGAAUGGGUGGCAGAACCAGAACUAGAGUUCAGAUGUCCCUCUGUCAGCCCAAGGCUUGUUUUCAUUACGGCCUUGUUAUCUGCCUGAUUGCAAACCCAAUCCCCCCUUCUCUCUAUGUCUUGGGUUCGGGAACCACUCCUGGCCUGAGCAGAGCAGGAAUAAAGCAGCAGGGCCAGUCUAAAGUCUGCACAUACUAACCAUGUGGCCAAAGGCAGGCCUGUUAAUACUUCUAAGCCUCAGUCUCCUUCUCUAUAGAGUGGGAAUGAUGUUUUCUGCUCUUCCUAACACACAGGGUUGCUUUGUAAAUUAAAUGAGAUAAUGUGCAUCAAAUAGGCUUUGAAAAACCUUUUAAAUAUGCUUAAAAUGGAAGGGUUCUUGAGGGUUGGGGUAUGGUUGAAUAGGUGAAGCACAGGGGUUUUCUUAGGUGGGUGAAAUUAUUCUGUAUGAUAUUGCAGGUAGAUACCUGACACUAUGUACUUGUCAAGACCUGUAGAAAUGUAUAGCACAAAGAGUACAUUUUUACACAAAAUAAAAGAAUCAUUUAGGAGAUCAGAGGAUACGAAGAUGGAAUGCAAAAUGUGACAAAACUAUUUAACUGGAUUAAAAACAUGUAAAACAACUUCACUGAAGUGGGGGAGGGGUGGGAGUUUUUGAUCUAAGCAACUUUGGAAAUGAGUGGAGUCUAUAAGACUAAAGACUAAAGAAACUGUGCCUAAGCACUAUACUCUAGUUGAUAAAGUAGCUUCUCAUGGAGUGUGGUUAACAAUUCCAGUACCACUAUACAUGUGUAUUGGAACUGAAUGAGUAAGUCAAUGGAUAGUGGAUGGUAACAGACAGGUUUCUCACUGUGGGAGUGGAAGGUUACAGACAGGCAAGGGGAGAAGGCUAGAAUGAUCCUUGUGAUAAUUUAUUAGAGUUGUAAUAUUAGUAUGAAAUCAAGUUUAGAUUGCACUCCAUCCAGGGCAACAAGAGCGGAACUCCGUCUCAAAAAAAAAAAGGUACCUCUCCCUCUCCCUCCCCC